GUUGACCAGGCUGGUCUUGAACUCCUGACCUCAAGCCAUCUGCCCACCUUGGCCUCCCAAAGUUCUGGGAUUAUUUUUUAAGCAGUUUUGAUAGGUGUGUACCUAGUAGUGCUCUGUGGUUUAAUUUGCAUUUCCCAGGGAGUGGGGGCACUGCCUGUCUUCUCACGCCUCAGUUGCUUGUUGCUGUGACGGUCGCCCACUCCUCCUGCCAGUGUCUGUGCUGCUCACGGUAGCUGCAUCAGCUUCACGCUGUCCGCCCUUCGCCACCCACCGCGCCUGCUGCUCAGGAAUGUUCCAAGCAACUUGGUGGUAACAGAAGCUGAGAACAGCCCAGAUGUCCUUCGGUGCAAGAGUGGAUGGAUCAGUUGUGGUCUAUUCACAGAAUAGAAUGUGACCACACUGGAGAUGAAUGAAUUGUAGCUACAAUCUGCAGUGUAGACGAAUCUUAGGAACGUAGGCGUUUCAGAAGCAGAUCAAGCCAGGCACGAUGCUGUGUGCCUAUAGUCCCAGCUACUCAGAGCCUGAAGGUGGGAGAUCACUUCAGCCUGGGAGUUUGAGGCCAGCCUGGGCAACAUAGCAAGACCCUGUCUCAAAGGAAAAAAAAAGCAGAUUACAGAAAAGUAAAUCCAGUGCUAGGCCGUAUUUUUAAGCUCAAAAAAUUAAAACUAAUUAGCGUUUAGGGAUAAACAUGAGGUAAUUUUUUAGAAGCAAGAGAAUAGCAUUGAAUUUAAGGUAUAUAUGGGGAAAAUGAAACUUCCAAGUUAUUGAUAAUUUUCCAGUUUUUAAAUUAGAGACGGGAUCAUGGUGUUUAUGCGUCAUAAUUUAUAUGUUCCAUAUAUUUUUUGUUGUUUUUUUGAGACGGAGUCUCGCUCUGUCACCCAUGCUGGAGUGCAGUGGCGCGAUCUCGGCUCACGGCAAGCUCUACCUCCCAGGUUUACACCAUUCUCCGCCUCAGCCUCCCGAGUAGCUGGGACUACAGGCGCCCACCACCAUGCCUGGCUAAUGUUUUUGUAUUUUUGUAGAGACGGGGUUUCACUGUGUUAGCCAGGAUGGUCUCGAUCUCCUGACCUUGUGACCCGCCCGCCUUGGCCUCCCAAAGUGCUGGGAUUACAGGCGUGAGCCACCACGCCCGGCUGAUAUGUUCCAUAUAUUUCUUUCUGUAUUUCACAUAAUACAUAGUAAAAUAUUUAAAACAGAACAAAAAUAGACUUCCUUUUAAGAUGUUUUCAUAUCUGUUCUUACAAAGUUGGCCACAGUUUUUCCCCAACAGUAGUUUGAGUUCAGCAGCAGCUCUUUUAUAAAACGUUUGCUGCACACACUGAGAUUGCACCUGGAAGUACAGAAAUAAGAACACACGUAUUUUAUUUUAUUUUUUUACCCCUGAAGAUCUUUAAGUCUUCUGAGGAGCAUGGACCUGCUAGACUGCAAGCUGCUGCAUUCUGAGGAGCAGGGACCUGCUAAACUGCAAGCUGCCGCAGGCGGAGAUUUUUGCCUGUUUGGUUUAUUUUGUUACCACUGAGUCCCCAGCUCUGAGAACAGAGCGAGGCAUGUGAUCGAUGCAUCGUAACUGUUGAGCAAAUGAAUGCUGAGCUGUGAUGGCACCGACGUGUCCGGGGAGAGGACGCACCCGGCUGUGUGGACAUGUGCCCAGGGCCCAGGACAGCGCCACGGAAGAGGACACACCCGGCUGUGUGGACAUGUGCCCAGGGCCCGGGACAGCGCCACGGAAGAGGACGCACCCGGCUGUGUGCACAUGUGCCCAGGGCCCGGGACAGCGCCACGGAAGAGGACGCACCCGGCUGUGUGCACAUGUGCCCAGGGCCCGGGACAGCGCCACGGAAGAGGACGCACCCGGCUGUGUGCACAUGUGCCCAGGGCCCGGGACAGCGCCACGGAAGAGGACGCACCCGGCUGUGUGGACAUGUGCCCAGGGCCCGGGACAGCGCCACGGAAGAGGACGCACAGGACAGCGCCACGGAAGAGGACGCACCCGGCUGUGUGCACAUGUGCCCAGGGCCCGGGACAGCGCCACGGAAGAGGACGCACCCGGCUGUGUGCACAUGUGCCCAGGGCCCGGGACAGCGCCAUGGAAGAGGACGCACCCGGCUGUGUGCACAUGUGCCCAGGGCCCGGGACAGCGCCACGGAAGAGGACGCACCCGGCUGUGUGCACAUGUGCCCAGGGCCCGGGACAGCGCCACGGAAGAGGAUGCACCCGGCUGUGUGGACAUGUGCCCAGGGCCCGGGACAGCGCCACGGAAGAGGACGCACCCGGCUGUGUGGACAUGUGCCCAGGGCCCGGGACAGCGCCACGGAAGAGGACGCACCCGGCUGUGUGGACAUGUGCCCAGGGCCCGGGACAGCGCCACGGAAGAGGACGCACAGGACAGCGCCACGGAAGAGGACGCACCCGGCUGUGUGGCAGGGGAGGUUCCCAAGAGCAGGCUCAGGGCUCUGGGGUCUGAGUGAGGGCUCUCCAGCCAGCAGGGAGCAGGGCAGGGUGUUGAAGAGACGGCAGGUGCGUCAGGGGCUGACGUGGGACCCGGCACUCUGUGCUCUGUGUCUGCCCGGGAACAGGUAGUCCUGCGUCGGACCGGGAAGUGUGGUGGGUGUGGUGGGGGAAGGGGCUGGCGUCAGCAGGGCUCUCGUCCGCCAACGUCUGGUGGGGAUGCCCGCCA